GCACUUGAUAAGAUACCAGCAGCACUGGCCAAAUGUUGCACAUGGUUAUGAGUUGGGCAUACCGAGGUUUUAUAUUUCAGGGCCUCUGAAAUCAAGGACUUCUGAAUGAGACACCAGUCUCUUUCACAUAUGACAUUAAAAUGUCAAAGCAAUAUUAUUCCUUUAAAAAAGGGGUAGGGAGUGGACUGGAAGAUAAUACAUUCAUGACAUUAUGGGACUUUCUAGAGUCCUGGAUUAUUCAAAAUGAUUGGGUGGCAAUUUUCUUUAUAAUUUUACUAGGAAUUAUUUUUGAGAUAAUACUCAUGAAAGCUUGUGCAUCCUUUUGGAAGAAGCCCACACUUCCUGAAAAGGGUAGUUCAGAUGUCCAGGAGACGGAAGACAGUUGCCCCAAAAGCAGGAAACUUGCUCCAGAGAAUUGGUCAGUUAUUAAUUCAUCUUCAGGAGAAAGAGUUGGCACCUUUUUAGAAAAAAGAAUUACUUCAUCACUUACAUCUGAAGAAAAGGAAUGUAACUUUGAAGAUAGAAUUUUAUUCUCACGUGAAAUACUAUGGUCAGGUACUAGUGAAAGUGAAGAUCAAGUAAGUCCCUCUAGUGAAAGUCAUGUGCCAUCUUCAAAUGGAAUCAGCUCAUCUUUGCCAUUGUUUUAUUCAGAAGUAGAGGAAACGUGUCUAAGCCAUACAGAGCAUCCAGACAGAGAAUAUGAAACAAUACAAUUUUCCUCCAAGAAAUUAUUUUCAAUGAUGAAAACCAACAAAAACAAAAAUUCAGGAUUUUCUUCUGAUCUUAGCUUUUCAGCAUCUAGAUUCACUGUAGAAAAUGAAGAUCUAGAUGUGGCACCUUGCCCUCUUGCCCACUUAUUUCUUUCUAGAGAUCAAGUUAGACUUCUGGAAGAAAAUGUGAGGAAUCAAAUUCCUUCAAAACCCAAAACUAAGUUAGGGAGCAGAACUACUUAUCAAUGCUCAAGAUCUCAAGAGUCCUUGAAUCAGAAUCAACCUUCUGUUGGAAUGGUUAUUUCUGUCCAAGCACAGGAUUCUUUUCCAGGACAAAAUGCUUUUCAGAAUCAAGGUCUUUAUGAAGUCCAAUUUACUAGUCAAGCCCAAUAUAUAAAUCAUAACCAAGAAUCAAUUAAGAGCCAGCCUGAGAGCAAAGCCAGCAACUUUGCCCAGCCUGAAGAUGUGAUGAAGAAGCCAUUUUCUAGCAGCACACAAGACUCCUUCCAGUCCCAAGAUCUGGAUAGGAACCAACAUUUUGUUGAAGUUCCAUCAAUUGUUGAGGCAAAAUAUUCAGUAAAGGGCCUGGAGUCUGAUGAACACUUAGGUGAGGACCAACAUUGUGUUUGGUUUAUAGAUUCAAACAAGGUUAAAUAUUCAAUUAAGGGGCAAGACACUAUUUUUAAGAAUGCUGAAUUUCUCGUUUUAACUCUGAAUCCAAAUUUAGUCACUGAAGAUAUGCCACAACUAAGGAGUGUAAAAGCACAAGGCCAGCAACAAAUUGUUUCAUCAGAAUUGAACCAGGAUUCUGUAUAUAGCUCAGUGCCUCUUUUGUCUACCAUUAAAGGGCAGAAAAAUAGAAGAAAAACACCAGACAGUAAAAGCAAACUCAGUCUUAAUGUUCCAUCUCUAAAAGCCAAAAAAACACCAACUUCACAAGUAUUUCAAAUCACAGUAUGUCACACUUUAAAAAAUAGGAAUGAGUUAGGAUGCAAGAAUAACACUGAGAAGAAAGAAUUACAUGAAAGGAAAGAUAUAUCAGAUAUAGCUUUGCAUCUUAUUUCUGUUUCCAAGCUUAUUCUGCCUUAUGUUAAAAAUUAUUCCAGAAAACAACUAGUGAAAGUCAUGCCGGGUUUAAUAAAAUGUGGACAUUUUCUGCAGAAGCAAAAUAAGUCACCAGAUACAGAGAAAAUCAAUUAUGCAGGUCCUCUUGAGGAGACAGGAAUCUCAGAUAUUACUAAAAAGGAAAAGGAGUAUGACAAAGAAAACAAAAGACUAAAAAACAUUUCACCAAAAAUGUUACCUCAGCUAGAACAAUCCUUCAUGGUCAACACUGUUCAACUAAAAGCACCUUGUUUACUAGUAGAAACAAAUGGGAAGAGUAAAGAAUCUCUUAAAGACUCAAUUACACAAGCAAAGGGAAUUGGUAUUACAGAAUUUCAUGUUCUAAAUAGUAAAAAACCAUUUGAUCUCCAUAUUCCAAAGCACAAGACAUCUUUAGAAGAAGCUAUAUCAAAACCUAUGCAGAAACUUGUUUCCUCUCCUGAAAUGGAAUCGAACAAUAGAAUGAAAAUACAGGAGGACCUACAAAGUUCAGAAAAUUCCCAUCUUCAACUUUCAAAUGGAGAGGAGUUACCAACCAGUACACCAAAAACGCAAAGGUGCUUUCCAAGGGAAAAUACACAGAAACAAAAAGAUUUUUUGGAACUUGUUCUGGAGUUGUCAAAUGUCGGUUUGCUCAUUUCCCCAGGAAGCAAAAUGCAUAAAAGCAGUGAAGAAUUAGAAGCCAUAAAAAUUCAAGUGAAUACAGAAAGUGUAAAUCUGAAGGAAAGUAAACCAUUGAUACUUAAUGUUACAGAAGACAGUGACCUACGUGAAAGUGAGGAACUGGAAUGCAACACUGGAAGUAACAUAACAAAUAUGCAUCAAGAUAAAGAAACGUCUGAUGCAUUUCACAGUGCCACUUACACUACCAUUUCUCAACUACCUGAUACAGAAACACAUAGCAUAUCAAAAGCCAAGGCAGACACAUUAAGAAUAAUAAGGCUCAGUCAUUCAGCAUCAAAGCAAGAGAAAUUACCAGAUGAGAAGGAAACACAGAACGCAGAAUACAUUGAUAAGAGCUGUACAUUUAAAAAGCCACAACAAUGUGAUAGAAAGGAACAGGAGAAAGAGGCAAAUUCAGAGCUGACACAAGGCUUCAGGUUCAGCAUACAUCUAAAGCAAAAGCCCAAGUAUGUCAAAUUCCAAAUGGAACAGAUCAGUUCAGGAAGUAGUAAAGCCCCAAAUAAAGAGCAAGAAGUCCAACCACAAACUCUUUCUACACAAACUAUUUUGGAGAAUAGUCCAUGCCCCAUGAUGGAUCCAUUUCAAGUUGAGAAGGUGAAGCAAAGCACAGAUAGACCUACAGACAGAGAGAGUGCCGGAGAUCCAAAGAAUCCACUUACAAUGCCAGAGAACUUGCCAGUUGGUGAACUUUUAAUUGAAACAACAGAGUAUAGUGUCCCAUUUGGUGGAAACCUCCAAAAGACAACGGAUAGUCAUAUUGCAGAAGAAAAGGAAGAUGUAAAAAGAUAUUUACCUGCAGUUGCCCUGGGGUCUUUCAAUAACCACUUGCUUACUUUACCAUAUUUUAAAAGGCAGGAAAUUAAAAAAAAAUUAUCAGAAACAAAAAGUGUACUCAGUGUCAAAUAUGUAAUUAUGAAAGUAAAGAAGCCAGCAAUCUCACUGAUGCCUUAUAUUAAUAUAUGUGGUACUUCAAACCACAGGAAAAAAAUGGGAGGCAAUUUUGAAAUUAUAAUUAAACAGAUACUGCAAGAUAAAAUUGCAGCAGGUAUGCUUCUGAAUGUUAUUUACCCUCCCAUGUCUAUUUUGCCUAAUACUAGAAUGUAUAGCAGAUUAAAUGCAGAGAAUCACAGUCAUAUCAAGCUAGUCCAAGAGGAAUCCCAAAUUGAAAGGGAAGAAAAGUAUCCAUAUUUCAUUAAUGAGGGAAAUGAAUCCCAAAACACACUAGAUGCUAAAUUGCAAGAUGAAGUAAAAGGCGUCAAAGAAACUCUACCAAAAGCAGUCCUGCAUGAUAGCUGCAACCUUGGACUUGAUGCACAUCUAGAGAAGGAGAUUAAAACAGAGAAAGAAAUGCAUCAACCAAUCCCAUUCACAGAAACUAUUAUUGAGUCUGUUGUUUCUCCCAUAAUGGAACUAUCUCAUGCUGAGAAUGUGAAGAGUACUCAAAAAACACAAACAGACUGCAAAUGCACUGCAGAUUCAGAGACGCCUUCUCCAAUAUCAGGAAAAUCACUGAUUGGAGACCCUUUAAACCAAACAAGAGAAAGUUAUAUUCCAAGUAAUGGAAGUGAUACAAGAGAAAUGGGUUACUGUUUUGCAGAAGAAAAGACAGAAAUACCAAAAGAUUUACCAGCAACUUCGCCAGAGACUUUCAAUUAUUGCACUCCUGUUUUAUCUUGUUCUAAAGUGAUGAAAAAGAGAGUAACAUUUGCACUCACAACAAGUACAGCGAAGCCCAAAUGUGUAAAUACAAAGGCUGUGAAGCCAUCAAUCUCAGAGACAGUCAGUGUCACAAGCCACAGAAAGAAAUCAGAAUUAGACUUUAAGACUAAGUUUAAAAAGAUAAACCAAACUAAAGGAUUGGUACCUGAAUGUCUAAAUACCCUUUGCUCUCCAAUGCAUAGCAGAUUGCAGAGAGAGUUCUGUCUCCCUGCGUCUCAAUUAAAGCAAGGAGAAACAGCAGAUAAGACAUACACUGAUGUCUUUGCUAAGAAUAGCAUAUCCCAUGACAGAGAGGAAAAAUUGCAAGAUGGAAAGGAAGAGGAACAUAAAGUUUUAUUAGAAGCAGCGCCACAGCUGAGCCAGCACCUGGGGUCUGAGGCGGGUCAAAUGAAGGAAAUCCAUCUUGAAUCAGACCCAGUGCUGAACUGUUUAACACUGGAGCUACAUAUUAAUGGACAACGUUUGCAGCACCAAACAGGUUUUGAACAAACUACUUUAGAGACUAGUCUCCAAAUGGGUCCUUUAGAAGCUGAAGAACUACAAAAAGCCAACGAAACAGAAAAUGACAUAAAAGUCCUUGGAGGUCCUAAGAUUCCACCUCCCAAAGCUUUACAGGCUCUGGAGAACAGCGAUGGCUUAAUACUCAAUGCAUAUCAGAAGGAUAAUGAGCUUGUCAAAUCAGAUGAGGAACUGAACCAACCAGGAAGUACAAAUAUUCAGGUACAACCACAAACACAUUUUACACAAACUAUUUUGAAGUCUACUUCAUGCCCUACACUGGAUCAAUUUCCAUUUGAAAAGGUAGAGAGUCAUGUUAGGUUUUCACCUCUAAAGUCUGGGGAAGCAAAGGUUGAUGAAAUCAUAUUUUAUGCAAGAGAAGGUGGUAUCUCAUCUGAUUCUAGCCAUCAAAAGGAACAGGCUGGUGGUACUGAAAAGAAAGAGACAGCGAUUUUUGGUUCCUGCAUGCCUGCUUUAUCUACACCUAAAACGACGAGAAACUUAAAACAAUUUUCAGACAUGAAAACUUUAGUGAAUCCCAAAUGUGGAAUUAUAAAGGCAAAGAAGCCAUCAAUUUCAUACAUGCUCAAUAUCAGGGCUGGUGCUGGUCCGAAACGUAGAAAAGAACUGAGCUGUAACUUGACAACCAAAAUGAAAGAACUGCAUCAAGGCAAAAAGGGGGUAGAUGAAACAUAUGCUUUCCUGACUAUGACACCUGACAUUAACAAGUAUAGCAAGGUAGAAACAGAAAAAGACACGCUAAGAGAAAAAAGACUCAGUUCUACUCAAGUAAAGCAAGAUACAUCUCCACAUGAAGAUAGUAUUACUUCACGUGACAUUAAAGAAACCCUUCUUCAAGAUGAAGAGCAAGAAGAAAGGAAACAGGAGGCAUUGUUAAAAGUAAUUCCACAGCACCUGCAACAUUUCAUGUUCCGUUCAGGUCAGGGGAAGGAUCUUGACUUUCACAAAUUAGAAAACCAAGGAAGUAGGAAAAUUCUGUUUGUUACCAAACAAGAUGUCCCACAGCAACUUCAGCCUGCAGAGCCAAUACAAAGAGAGGAGACAAAGAAAUGCCUCCAGACCCAAAAUGGCACAAUAUGUACAGUAAAUUCAAAACUUCUUCCUCUAAAAUCAGAGGACUCAGUAAAUGGUGAAGUUUUAACUGGUGCAAUAAAACGUGGUGUACCAACUGAUAGGAAAUGUAUGGGGGAACAGCACAAUUCAGGUAAAGGGGAAAAGGCAGAGUUUAAUAAAGAUCUACAAGCAACUGUCCUGGAGUUACAGAAAUCACCACAUGGUGGGGAGGCACAGAAGGCCAAUUUGACUGACAUGGAAAGUGGAUCUAGUAAUGCAAUGAACAUGAAUGUACAACAUGAAAGGGAAGAUAAAAAUAUUCAAAAAAUGUUAACAGAAUCAGUUCCAUGCUAUAGUCAACACCUCCGUUUCAGUACACAUCAAAUGAAAGAUCCUGACCCUUGCAAAUCAGGAUCUGAACCGAAGAGUCCCGAAGGCAGAUCUUGGAAUUUGUCUCACAUAGUGCAAAAAACAAAGCAAGAAACACACUUUAGAGAAACUGUUUUAGAGCCUAUUUCUGGAUACAUGAUGAAACAAAGUCCUCAUAUGCAAGAAGGAAUAAAAUGUAUGGAAGGUCUAAAGACUUCAUUUCCCAAAACAGGGAAAUCAAAGAUUGGUUCAAUACCACGUGAUACCCCUUGGGAUGAAAAUCCUAGAAGGAAAUGGGAUAGUUCUAUUUCUGAGAAAACUGCAUGGAAUCAAAAAAACUUACAAACAGUCUUAAAACCUUUAGAUUUCUCCAGCCUCAUGUCAUCUGAAUAUGAAAGCCGGAGCUAUACAUUAGAGUUUAUAGGCAAGAAAAGUAUGAGUCCCAAAUGUGUAACUUUGAAGGCAAAGCAACUACGAAUUUUGCAGUUGUUUAAUAUCAUAAGAUAUUCUACAGAAAACCACAGAAAGAAAAAGCAACACCGUUUUAAGUACAAGAUGAAAGGGAAGCAAUGGUACACAAGUAUAGGAGAGGCAUUACUCAGUGCCACUGAAUAUGCUAAGAGUACAACAUCCAAAUCAAUGAUUGAUAAACUCUUAUACAAUACAGCAGCGAGGUGCAUUCUAUCUAACAGAACACGCCGACAAAAUCUGGAUGGUCAUAUUACAGAGGAAAAGGAAGAGGUACAAGAAAAUGUAGCUGCAAUUUUCUUGGGUCUUUUAGAUUUCUUCAUGCCUGUUUUAUCUGACUCUAAAAACCAGAGGAACACAGCACAGUUAUCAGAAAAAGAAAUUAUAUUCAAUGCCAAAUGUUUAACUAUGAAGGAAAAGAAGUCGUCAAUUUCACAGAUACAUAAAAUCAAUAGAGAGUCUACCAGAAAACAUAGGAAGAAAUGUAAAUCCUAUUUAAAAACUGUAUCCAACAGAAAGUGCCAAGAAAAUCAUGGUCAUAUUACAGAGGAAGAGGAAGAAGUACAAGAAAACUCACCUGCAACUUUCCUGGGUCCUUUAGAUUUCUUCAUGCCUGUUUUAUCUGACUCUAAAAACCAGAUAAACACAAUACAGUUAUCAGAAAGGAAAAUUAUAUUGAAUCCCAAAUGUUUAACUAUGAAGGAAAAGAAACCACCAAUUUCACAGAUACAUAAAAUCAGUGGGCAGUUUACUACAAAACAUAGGAAGAAACUUGAAUCCAAUUUAAAAACCAAACUGAAAGCAAUGUGGCAAGGUGAAAAUGUGGCUGAUACAUUUCCAAAUACAACUUCCUUCACUCCAGAUUCCUCUGACAUUAAAAGGCAAAGUGGAUUCCAAACAGAGAUAGACAUGAGAAUAUCAGGGUUAAGUCAUACACAACCAACACAAAUAGAGUCACUAGCUGAAGGGAUAGCAAGGUAUUCUGAUCCCAUUGACAAGAGAAGAACUUCCAACUUGGUAAAGGGAGCAAAACUACAUGAUAGAGAAAGUGGGGAAGAGAAGCAAGAACAUCUUACAGAAAUGGAUCCAUUCUAUGCAGAAAACUUCAUGGCAAACACAUAUCUUAGAAAGGAUCGUCAUCUUGGUAAAUCAGAGGAUGUGCUUUUGGGAGAAACUUUUUUCUCAAAAAGUCAGAUUUACAAAGGGAAUUCAGAAAAAAAUGUAAAAAUAGAAAAAAACAAAAAUGGAAAAGAAAGUCUCAAAGUUGGGCUCGCAAGGAUGGAGAAAUCAGAUAAUUGUGCAGAACUGAGUGAGGCAACAGAUGAUGCCAUAUCAAACAAAUAUGAUAAACAGAACAUUGGCCAUUCUGUUUUAAAAGAAAAUGCUUUCUGUAAUUUGGCAGCAAUUGUCCCAGAUUCUGUUGGCAGGCAUUCACCUGCUUCAGAAGAAAUGAAAAGACAGAAUGGCAGACUUAAAAUGGCUGACAGGUCAAGUCCCCAAGGUAGACCUUUGCAGGCAAAGCAAUCAGCAGUUUCACAAUCACCUGAUACUGCAGGUUAUGCUGUUGUAAGCAAUAAUAAGGAGCAGAAACAGAACUUUAAAGCCCAGAAGACAGAAGCAGAAGUUGAUUUAAUAGAUCAAGAAGCAAAGAUAAAUGUUGCAGAAGAGUUUAAUCCAGAAUCUGUUUUUUUCUCUAAGAUACAUCCACUUCAAAUUGAAAACAAGAAAGAAUUUAAAACUGCAGACUGGAAAACAAGGGCAGAUCCCAAGACAUUUGCCCUGCCAAAGAAACAGCAAGAGCUGUGUGUCUCAGGAACUAUCUGGAGUUAUCCUAAUCCCUACACAUCUAUUUCUCCUAAAAUCAUAAGACAUAAAGAUAAGGCAAAGACAGCAGAUGUGGAAAGUACUAUGCAUACCAAACAGAUAAAAUUGAAGGCAAAAAGAAUAACAGUUUCCCAGCUGCUUGAGUAUGGUACUGCAAGCAAUAAAAAAGAACUGAGAGGUAACAUCCAGCAGCAGAAGUCAUUCCAGCUGAGUAAAAAUGCAGUACAUCGAGUUCUAAAGGCUGUUUAUGACUCUGGAUACUGUGUGUCUAGCAUUAAAAAGCUUACAGAAGUAAAAAUGGAGAAAGACAAGCCAAAAGACAGGACAUGCAUUCUUCCACAGCCAAAGCUGGAGAAACCACUAAAAGAAAUGCAAAGGUCAUUGUCAGGUUGUACUGAUAUGUCCAGCAUUCUUAGAAAACAGGAACAAGAUAUUAGAGAAAAGGAACAAAAACACCAAAGCAUUUCAGAAGACAUAUCCCAAUACUAUAUUGGACCGUUAAGGAUUAGUUCACAACAAAUCAAUUACAGUAGUUUCGAUGCCCCACGAAUUAGAACAGAUGAAGAACUUGAAUUCCUCAUUGCACAAAGAGCAAAGGAAAAAGAUGUGGGCAUUGCCAAACAUUCAGUUUCAAUUCCGUGGGAGAGAGAAGGAUCGAAGAGACUAGAUAUUCCACUAAACUCAAAAGGACAGAAUAUAUUUUUUACAGAGUUGGAUACUUCUCAACAGAAGACUUGCCAGGAGCAAGAAUUGCUGAAACAAGAAGAUAUUUCUAUGACAAACCUGGGGUCUAUGGCCUGCCCCAUUAUGGAACCUCUUCAUUUGGAAAACACAGGAAAGGUAACUGAGGAAGAAGAUGUGUACAUUAACAGAAAAAUUAGUUCACAUGUAUUGGGAAAAGAAGGAUUAAAGGAAACUGAUAUAUUUGUAGGUUCUAAAGGACAGAAAUUUCUUUGUACAAAUUCAGAGGUACAGCACAAAGUGCCUGCAGAGCAGAAAGAACAGGUGAAUCCAGAUCAUGUUCCCGAAAGUAUUCUGGAUUCUGAAUCUUUCCUCAGUAAGGACCCUCUUCACUUAAAACAGGCAGUGAAUACAGCAAGAAAAGAAAAUGUUACCAUCUCUGAAAGUUUCAAUGAAAAUCUUUGGGGAAAAGAGCAAUCAAAGUUGGAUAUUACAUUAAAAUCAAAUAGACAGAAAAUGGACUUUUCAAAAAAAUUGAGGAUGAAGCAUCUAAGUAAUUAUUAUCAGAAUAAAGAGAAUAUUCUGGAAUCUGUUCUCCCUUGCAUAUUGCAUCAACUUUAUAUUGAAAAUCCCAAGAAAGAAGGCUCAGCAGAAGAAAUCAUGAGUUCAAAAGUUCUAAGCCCAAUGGUAGAGAAAGCAUCACAUGAAGUAGGUAUUCCGGUGGAUCAACCUCCAUGUUCAGAAGGAAUACAUUUGAAUAUUAAAGGAAGAAAAGAACAUCCACAAGAAAGUACACACGAGGCUUUUCCAGCAUCUGUUUCUCACUCUUUAAUGGACGUACUUCAGAUUAAGUCACCAAAGGUAAAGAAAGCAUUAAAGGCAAUCAAUAGUUUAGGGUACCUCACUUCAAAUACAAAAGGAAUUGGCUUGCUUUUUCCAAGACAGGCAGAAAAGGAAGAAAAAUAUACAUACAAGGCUCUUCCAAAGCCUGCAUCUCACUCCAAAACAGAUCUAUUUCAGUUCAAUGCAUCUAUGCAACAAGAGAAAUUAGAUGCUAUGGAUAUUCCACAUUAUGACUAUUUAACUUCACAGACAAGAGAAGCAGUGAAACAAAUGGAUGUCAUAGUUGGAUAUACUCAAAACAGUAAAAAAAGACAAGACUUACUCAAAACAGGCCAAAAAUGGCAGUACCUACCAAUUUCCUAUGAGAACUUUUGGGAGCAUAUAUCUUGCCCUCAAAAGUAUCCCUGUCUCCUGCAACAUUUAAUGCCUCAGGAAAAGGAAGCAUUAUCAGAAGGAGGUAAUUUAUCAAGCCGGACACCAGGACUAGACUUGUUUUCUGCAGAUCAGCUAAGCACUAUAACUAAGAAUAGACUAGAAUGGAUUGUGCCCUUGAUUUCUCCAAGGCAGAUGAAAAAACAAGAUUCAAUGCUGCCUUUAGGAUCAUACCAUAAAACUAUAAAAUAUGCAAGUCUCUUAUUUCCAAAAGGAAUGAAAUCAUCAGAUGGGGUACAGGUCUUUGAUUUAAUAUCAAAUAAUAGCUCACCCAAGUUAAGACUUGGGAAGAAGAUAGAAACACAAAAGGCAAAUGAAAAGGUACAAAAAGAAGUAUGUCUGCCUAUAACAUUACAUUCUCUUUCUGCAUCCAUGCCUAUUUUGCAAGAAAGUAAAGGACAGAAGGAUAGCGUAGAACAAGUUAUUAGGAAAGGCGUGAUAUGCCACAAAAGGAGAACUUCGAAAUGGAAGAAAUCAGUAUUUUCACAUAUACUCAAUACCAGUGACUGUGGUGCCUCAAGUAACAGACUAGAAAUGCAGUGGAACAUGACAGACAAAAUGGUCAAUGUGAAACAUAGAAUGAGUGAAAUAGAUUUGGUUGCAGCAAAAAUAUGUGAGUCUAUUCUUUCUUUACCUCACUUCAAAUUGAAUAAAGAAACAAUUGAUGGGGUGAUCUCAAGUAAUGUUAAAAGUACAAAACAACACAUAUCACAGGGAAAGAAUGAUAGAGUAAAAGCAAUGGAUAUGAAAAGAAUAAAAAGCCCUAACAUCAUUUUGAAGCCAAGGAAGUCAUCACUGUCACAUAUACUCAGUAUAAAGGAAUUUCCUUUGCUGUUAGACAUUAUAAAACAAGAGGGCAAGAUGCAAGAAGGUAAAGGUAAAUCAAGUAUGAAACUGACAAACUUGUGUACUUCUUUACCAUCUCUAUCACAUAGUAAUUCAAAUUCAAGAACAAAAGCAGGUAAAGAUAAGUCAGGAACUCUAAAGGGCUGCCUUCCACCACUAAAGCUCCAGGCAUCAUCAAAUGCCAGAAGAGUAUCAUCUGCAGAGUCAAUUAAUAGAGACAGUUUAAGUAAUGUAAUAGAAUCAAAGUGUUUUCCACAGAAAAAGAAGGAAGAUAGAGAAAAUAUAGUAGAUGUGAAAGAUGUAAUGGGCCUCAAAUGUAUCACUUUGAAAGGAAAGAAAUCACUUUUUAGACAUUUACUGCAUGGAAAAGAACCACAACGGAGCAAUAAAAAACUAGAGAAAAUGACGCAGGAAGAUGAAAGUAAUCUAAAUGUAGUUCAGAAUAAACUCUGUGCUUCUAUUCUUUCUCCACCUCACUUGGAAUGGAAUCCUAGAAUAAAAGAGGUAUACAUGAGAGGAAUAACAAGAUUCUGUCUUUCAUCAUCAACACAGCAGGAAUUAUCAGAUACAAUGGAAAAAUGUGAGCAGCCAAUUGAUGAUAGUUUAAGCAGUAUUGAAAAAGCAAAACAUAUGCCGCAGAAAGACAAAGACAGAGUGGAAAAGGCUUUGGAAAAAAUCAUGCAUUCCAAAAGAAUAGCUUUGGAGGUGAAGCAGCCUUCAAUAUUCCAAGAAUUAGAGUUGAACAUCAAAGAAAAAGGAGGAAAGAUUCAGGAAGAUAAAGAAGUUGAGAUUUGGAGCAAACCUUUUGCUUCCAUCUCUUUUCUACCUUACUCUAAAGUGGGCACAAUAGAAGGAGAGGAAGCCAUGAGAAUAAAAAUGAGAUCCUCUUUUUCACAACCAAAUCUCCAAGAGUCAUCAGAUACAGAGAAAACAGCAUAUGAAAAGUGUAUUUCUGAUAAUAUCUCAAACAGUGUAAAAAAGGCCCUAGAAUCUAUAUUGCAAAAAGAACAGAGGCAAAAAAUGGAAAAAAUUAGGGCUUUGAAGAAAAUGAAAUCAUCAAUUUCACAGGGAAUUCAGUUGGACAUUAAAGAGCAAGAGAAAAGGAUAGAACAUAUUAAAGGUGAACCAAGUGUGCUUCUGACAAAUGCCUGCGCUUCCAUUCCUUCUCCUUCUCAUUUACAACUGGAUACAAGGAGAGAAAAAGCAGAGUAUGUCACUGAAAUAACAAGAUACUAUCUUCCAGAACUAUCACACCAAAAAUCAUCAGAGGCAGGGGAAAAAGCAGAUGGAGUGGCCAGUAAGGGUGAUAUCACAAUCAAAGUACAAAAAGCAAAAGAUUACAUGCAACAGAAAGAAGACGAUGAAGUAAAAAUAUCAGCUAAGAAAGACAUAAUGCAUCCAGAAGACAAAGGUCUGAAAGCAAAGAAGGCACUUUCACAGGACCUACCAUUGAAUACUAAAGAGCCAGGGAAAAUGGAUCAAGAAGCUCAGGAGCAAGGGAAAGAGGACAGAGAAGGUGAGGAGCAAGGGAAAGAGGACAGAAGAGGUGCAGGACAAGAAAAGGUUGAUAGAGAAGACAAAGAGCAAGGGAAAAUGGAUCACGAAGUUGAAGAGCAACAGAAAGCAGAUGGAGUAGGCAUAGAGCAAGGGAAAAUGGAUGGAGACAAGAAUGAACAGGAAAGAGUUCUGUUCCUAUAUUUGCCUUCCAAUUCUUCUCUAACCCAUUAUAUAUUGGACACAAGAAUAGAAGGAGAGGAAGACCAACAAGGAAUAAUCAGACCUGGUAUUUUACAACCAAGGCACCAGAAAUCAUCAGAGACAGGGAAAAAAGCAAAUGGGGUGCCCAGUGAGGGUGAUAGCGCAAGUGAAGUACAAAAAGCAAAAGAUUACAUGCAACAGAAAGAAGAGGAUGAAGUAAAAAUAUCAGCUGAGAAAGACUUAAUGCAUCCAGAAGACAAAGAUCUGAAAGGAAAGAAGGCACUUUCACAGAACCUACCACUGAAUCCUAAAGAGCCAGGGAAAAGGGAUGGAGAAGGCCAGGAGCAAGGGAAAGAGGACGGAGAAGGUGAGGAGCAAGGGAACAGGGAUGGAGAAACUGAAGAGCAACAGCAAGCAGAUGGAGUAGGCACAGAGCAAGAGAAAAGGGAUGGACACAAGAGUAAACAGGAAACAGUUCUCUUCCUACAUUUGCCUUCUGAGUCUUCUCUAACUUGUUAUGAAUUGAACACAAGAAAAGAAGGAGAGGAAGACUUACAAGGAAUAAUAAAAUCUGCUACUUUGCAACUAAGGCAGCAGAAAUCAUUUGAUGCAGGGAAAAUAGCACAUACAAAGUCUUUUGGGGUGGAUAGCUCAAAUGAUGUAAAAACAGUACAAGAAUACAAGCCACAGAAAGAAGUAGAUAGAGGAAAAACAGUAAGUGUGGAUUAUAUAAUGCAACCUGAAGGCACAAUUUUUGAGGCAGAGCAAUUAUCACUUCCACAUACACUCAAUAUCCCUGGCAGCAGUGGCUCAAAAACUAGAGAAGUACUAACAAACAUAAAAGAAAAAUUGAGACAUGUACAGGAAAGAAAAAGUGAACUGGAUGUGUUUCUGACAAUACCUUCUCUAUCUCACUGUAAAUUAGACAAACGAACAGCAGGCAAAAAAGAGGAACAAGGAGUAACAAGAUCUUUUCUUCCACCCUCAUGGCACAUGGAAUCAUCAGAUACAGGGAAAUUAAAAUAUACAUUGUCAUAUUUGAAUGAUAUCACAGGUGAUUCAAACAGAACAAAAUACAUGGCCCAGAUCCAAAAGGAUAAAGCAAAUAUUUCAGAGAAAAGUGUAAUGCAUCCCGAGUACAUAGCUGUAAAGGCAGAGAAAUCACCCCUUUCCCAUAUACUAAAAACAAAGGAACUGCAGGUGAACAUCAGUCAACAAGGGGAAAAGGCACAAGAAGGUGAGGUGGAAAUAGUUGUACUUCUGAGCAAAACUUGUCCUUUUGUCACUUCUUCAGCUUUCCUUGAGUUAGACUCAAUAAAAGAAGAGGAAGGUGAACCACGAAUAACAAGAAGCUUUAUGCCACAUCUUGAGAUCCAGGAAUCAUUGCCUUCAAGGCAAACAGCACCUACAAAGCCAACAGAGAGCCUUGUAAAGAAAGAGAAACAACUCCUUCCACAGAAAGAAGACAGAGUACAAACAGUAUCCAUGCAUGGCCUGAUGCACCCCAAUGGUGCCGUUUUCAAGGCAAAGACAUCAGCACCUCCACAAGUGUUCAGCAUCACUGAGCACAGUCCUCUGAGUAAGAGAAAGGAGCCACAGUGGGGCAUGAAAGAGAGAGCAGGACAGAAGCAGGACAGGACAGGACGUCCUCAUGUGAUUCUGACAAAAACUCAUCCAUUCAUGCCUUCUCUCUCUCACCAUAGAUUCUCUCCUUCACAACCAAAGCUUCCUAUAUCAUCAGGUGCAGGAAAAAGCAGACUUGCAAAUUCAAAUGAAGGUAUUAGCUCACAUAAAGUAAUACUAAAAGCAAACCAACAAAUGCCAUAUAAAGAGGCAAAGGACAGAGUAAAAAUAGAAGGCAGGGAAGGUAGAAUACUCCCCAAAAGGAUACAUUUGAGGGCAGAGGCACUCCCACUUGCACUUCUAUGCAAUGGAAAGAACUACUCUUUGCACAUUGAAGAGCAAGGGGAAGGAGUACAGGAAAGCAAAAAGGAACCUGGAGUGGUUCCGAGGAAAUCUGCUUCAUUCCCUCCUCCUCCAUUUUACCUGAAUUGUGACACUAGAAGGAAUGAAAAGGAAGGCACAUUAGGAAAAACACAAUUCAGUUUUCCACCACUAAAGAUUCAGGAUUCAUCAGAUUCAGGCAAAAAAGCAUAUACUGAGUCACUGCAUGGUUACACAUUAAGCAACUCAAAAGGACCAGUGCAACCCACAGCACAGGGAGAAGAGAAAGGUGGACUCAGAAUAGAUAUGGAAGACAAAAUGCUCCCCAAAUGUACAGACCUGAAAGCAAAGCAAUUACUACUCUCAGAUAUACUCAAUACCAAAAAAUUGCAGUGGAAAAGUAAAGAACAAAAGAGAAAGAUUCAGGAAGAUAAAAAUAAACAAGUUAAAGGACUGCCAAGCAUUAAUACUUCUUUACUUACUCCACCAUAUCUUAAGUUUGAUACAACAGAAGGACAGGAGAACGUGAUAAGAAUUGCAAAAGUGUCUCUCCCACAGUCACGGUCCAAGGAAUCAUCAGAUGCAGGGAGAAUAGCAUGUCCAGAAGCAACCCAUGGAGAACUUUCAAGUGAUGUAAAGCAAUUAAAAGCACACCUGCUACAGAAAGAAGAGAAGGAUAGAGAAAAAGUUGCGGAUAUGACCAGUGUACUGGAUCCCAACAAAAUGUAUUUGAAGGCAAAGAAAUCGCCUGUCUUACAUACGCACAGUUUCAGUGAUCUUCAGUGGAAAACUAGAGAGCAAGAGGAGGAAAAGGUCCAGAAAGUUAAAAGUGGGCCAGGUGUCAUGUUGUCUAAGAGUCCUUCUAGAUCCUCCCCACUUCACCUUAAUGUGAAUACAGGGUUUCAGGAGGAAAGCAUACCAAUAUUAACAAGACCCUCUUUUCCCCUAGUAAAACUCCAGGUAUCACCAGAUACUGAGGGAGGCACAUGUAUAAGGCCAAUUGCUGGUGAUAUUUUAAUCUAUCUACAAAAAGGAAAACAUGUGUCACAGAACAAGGAAGAGGAUGACGUGCAAAUAGUAAGCAUCUUAAUAUUCCCCAAACAUCAGGAAGAGAAGGUGCAGGAAUGUGAAGGUGAACCAGGUGUGGUUCUGACCAAAUCUACUUCAUUGCCAUCUCUAUCUCAACUAGAAUUGGAUAAAGAAACACAUUUAGGUAAUGAAAUGCUAAGACUUAAAAGACCUAUUUUGCGGAGAAUAUCACACAUAGGGGAGACUGUACAUAGAGAGUCCGUCGUUGGUGAUAUCCCAAAAGAUGUUAAAAAUGAAAAGCAACAUAUCCCUCAAAAAGAAGAGAGGAACCAAAAAAAAAUAAUCGAUAUGAGAGGCACAGAUAUAACUUUGAAGUCAAAGAAGUCACCUCGUUCCUGUAUGCUCCACAGAACAGAACUGCAUGUGAACAUUGGAGGGCAAGGACGAAAGGAACAUGAAGGUCAAGAUAAACCACCAGGUAUGAUUCAAAGAAAAAUGUGCAUACUCUUUUCCAAACCUUUGCCAUCUAACCUUAAACUGGAGAGAGCUACGCAUGCAGAUGAAGAAAGGCUUGGAGGUAAGACAUCCUUUGUACUUCCACUAAUGCCAUCAGCAUUACCAGAUACAGAGAAAACAGCAGAUGCAGAGGCAAGGAGUGGUGAUGUAAGAAAAGGAAAACCACAUAGGUCACAGAAAGAAAACAGGCAUGAAGUGAAAACGAUAGAUAUGAGGUUCAGGAUACACUGCCAAGAGGCAAGGAUUUCACCAAUGUCACAUAUCCUUAAUGCAAAGGAAUUAGUGUUGAAUAUUAACAAACUGGAGAAAAAAGUACACAAAGAUAAAGAUGAAGCAUGUGUGGUUCUGUCAAGGACUUUUCUUUCUAUACCGUCAGCACCUCCUCUUUAUCUGGAUUCAGGGAACAAAACAGACAAAGACACUCCAGGAAUUACAGGAUCAUCUUGUCCACAGCGAACUCUCCAUGUACCCUCAAAUACCCAGAAAAUAACAAAUAGAGACUCAGUUGAAGGCGUUGAUAAAAACGUUGUUAAGCAAGCAGAACAGUAUGUGCCCCGCCCAGAGGCAGAGCAACAGUUGACCUCAAACUUCAUGAUCAGCGUCCAGCAAAGGAACCAACCUUCACGAGUCAGGUCAGAAGAAGAUUUGAAUCAGUUAGUUUUAAACUCACGGGAUGAGGACAUUUAUUUCACAGGGUUUGGUACCAUAAGAAGUGGGAAAAGGCCGGAAUGGCUCUUUACAGGGAAAAAGGCUCAGCCUGUAAAAUACAAAACAGAAACUUUAACUGCGUUUCUUUCCUAUCCCACAAUGGAUGCAACUAAAAUGGGAGGUCUGGAAGAAGACACUGAAAUAAUGGAUAACUUAAACCAUAAAAUCAGUCCUAAGGCUUCAGUUUCACUGAUAAGGAAAAUAUCUAAGGAACUGUAUGUCACACUUGGCACCCCUGCAAAUUCAAAAGGAUUUUCUGUUUCAGAGAGAUACGCUCACCAGCAAGAAACUUCAUCGAAAGUAUCUCCAGAACUUGCAGGUUCAUGUAAAUUUGAUAAGCCAAAGGAAGAUGGACAAAGUAAUGAUAGAAUCAGCAAAAUGUUUUCUCCCAAAGUGUUAGCACCACAGACAAAGGGAUCACUCAAAAAAAUAAGUAUCGUCACCAACUGGAAUGCCCCCCAAAAUAUAGAAGAACAAGAUAUUGUCAUGAAAAAGCAAGUGAUCCGACGGUGUGAACAUGGGCACAAGACCAGGACGAACACUAUCCUUUCUAAGUUUCCCCUUCAAAGUGGAAAGCAGAAGACACCAUCGGAAACAGAUGUGGACAAGAAAACAACAGCGCACCUCAGCCUACAGAUGCUACCAGGAAUACACAUGGAUAUGACAGAGAUUGACCCUGCAAAAGGGGGAAGGAAGCAGGCAUUGCUCAUUUCAGAACAAGAGGAAGGUGUUCUGGAAUUUCUUCCGAAGUCCCUAUUCCCUCCCUGGACUUUUCAAUUUCAAUCAGGGGAUCUGGAGGAAAAACAUCAAACAGACGCAAACACCAAUAUAAAUCUAGAGCAGAAAAAAUUAGAAAUGGACAAUGAUAGUACUGUGAAUCAGAAAGAAGGGAAAUUAAAAAUAGGCACAAACAGAGCUUUACAUCUGCAAGAAGAGAAAACAGAGAUGCACAAGGCCAGGACUGCCAAUCUGGAGAAGGAGAGAGGAAGAAUGGACACAAGCAGUAGUGCACACCCGCAUCUUCUAUCUCUAAAGGCAGAGGAAUCUCAAAUGAAGACUCAAGUCAUCACUCAUAGGGAGAACAGCCGCCUAAUCAUGCAAAAGCAGAAAAAAGAACUAGAAGCAUCUAAUGCAAAACAAAGCAUUCAACUACAAAAAUUAUUUCAAAGAAAUGUUCUGGAUUCAUUUUAUUCAUAUGUUCCUCUUUCUCCCAAACGUAAAGAUCAGAAAGGCAGAUUAACAAUAAGAGAUCUGAAAAGAGAAUUGAGCACCAAAUAUUUAACUAUGAAAAUCCAGAAUCACCCAAUUCCACAGAUGCUUAAUAUCACGGGGCGUGGUACACCAAGCAAUAGAAAGAAAUUAGAGUAUGAUGUUAAGUUAAAGAACAUAGCUUCGUGGAGUAAAGAUGUCUCAGGAAUAUUUAUCAGAAGUCUUUCUAUUUCCAUCAUGCGUUCACCUCACACUGACCCUAAGACAAACCUAGAAAGAGAAAAGAGAAUCUGUCUUCCUAAAUUCCAGGAAAAAUCACCAAACACUAGUGAAAUGUCUAAGAGAGACACUUUAACAAUUGUAAAAGGGGAACAGAAUUUUACAAACACAGUUCCACAAGAUCCCCAGCCCUUUGCAGUGGACAAACAACAAAUGCAGAAACUUCCUAAUGUCAAAUCAGAAGCAAACCUCAGAAGUGAAAUGAAUAAAAAAUACUUAAAGGCACAAACAAAAGAACGGAUUGUUCCAGAGCAUGAUGUCUCAAGGAUCAUUAAAAAACCAGACUUACGUAUCAUCGAGCAGGAAGAAAAGAUUCUAAAACGCAUUCUGACACCCACAGAGUGUCCAUCUAUGCUUGAAGAUCCAAAGUUACCCAAGCAAAGGGAUCAGAGUGAACCAGUAUGGGACAUGACCACACAAAAGGUUCAGCAGCAAAAAGCUUUCCCAGGAACUGUGCCCAUACCGCCUCAAGUUAAAAGUAGCGAAGUCAAAAUAGUUGCAGACAGUACAAAUGCAGAACAUUUACUUCCCAUUUGUGAAGCAACCAAAGCUAUCUCUGAGUCCCAGGUUAAAAAUAUGAUCCAAGACAAAGUUUCUUCUGAUAAACUAGAUAACAUACAAGCCUAUAAGCCUGACGACUUGAAGUCACCACCUUUUCCAGAGGGUCCAGAUACAAUAUCAACAGCAAUAUAUCCCAAAACGCAGCACAAAUCCCUUUUAGAACAGUUUACUCCCAAAGAAAAAAAUAAGCUUACUAGUCAUUUAGAGUCAAAAGCACUUGAAAUACAACUGAAUCUGAUACCAGAGAUGGCAAGGAAAUCUUUACAAAUGUUCAACUUUUAUCCAAAAGGGACUAUUUCAAAAGAUAACAGUUGGAGGUUCUAUUCUAGACAUAAAACAAUGAACUUUAUGUCUCUAGAAGGGACUGAUACCAUAGAACCUAACUCAAAACAUAAACACCAAAAGGAUUCACCUCUUGCCAGCAAUAUGAAGACACUGAUUGUUGAUGUUUCAAGUGACAGUGAGGAGACAAUCACAAAGCUACAGAGUAUUAAUAAGCUAGAAAAUGGAACAUCUGCAGUGACUUCUGCUAGUGAGAUGCUAUUGCCUCAUACCCUCCAAAACCACUCAGUAAAAGAAAAAGGCAAACUCCUCAUGCACUUUUCUGUGAAAACAUUGGAGAUACAAAUGAAAGCCUUUCCCAGAAUUGUAAGAGAAUCUUAUGCAAUGACCAGUGCUCAUGAGAGAAAGAAACCCUUAUCUAACUGUAUUCAUCCUGGUUUCACAGGACCAAAACGACAAAACAGAAUUUUGUUACUUUCUGAGGAGAAAUCUCUCCAUCAAAUAGAUCUUGAUUUACAAUACAAAUACCUUCGUUUUCUCCUGGGGCUUCCUGUUGGAAGUACGUUCCCUAAGCCAAAUGUACUUCCCAAACAUAGUAAGUUAAACACAAUUGCAGUGUGUAAAAACGUAAAUGCUGGUGGACAAAGUGGUAGUCUUUCCAUUGAUACAGAACUGUUAGAACAACAUAUUUCUUUCAAAAAGCAAAGUCCCCAUGAAAACUCAUCACUCAUCAGAAAAUUCCCACAGCCAACCCUUGUGUGUGCUUCUGACCGUGAUCUGCACAGCCCGAGGAAGAAAGAUACUCAAGUUCUUUCAGAGUCAGAAUUCCAUGUGACUCCAGAAAAAAACAAACAAUAUCAUGUAUGGUUUCAAGAAAGAAAUACAUGUGAAUCUGUUGAUUUAAGGACCCAGAGAAAUGCUACUGGUUCAGCUGUUUCAUGUGAAACUCAGAUUUCUGAAGAUUUUGUUGAUAUUCAGACAGAUAUUGAGAGUCCAGCUGACUUGGACGAGUGUUCAUGUCUUGAAGUAAGUGAGAGUGAGGAAUGUGUGUUUCUGGAAGCCAACUCUUAUUUAAGUCAGGAAUCAGAAAACAUUCUAUUUGAAUUACAGACAGGCAUUCCUUUGGAAAAUGUCUACAAAAUCACGACUGAUUUGAAAUCAUUUUACAGUGAAGAUUCAGGUUCCCAUUGUACUAGAGAGUGCAGAAAGGAAACCUUAAUUAUUACACCACCUUCCUGUAAGUCCCACAAAAGCAGGAAAUAUAGAUCAUCUUCCAAAAUGAAAUCUCCUGACUGGUUGUGUCAUAGUUCAUCAAAUACUGCGGAAAUUCAGUCUAGGUCAUCUAGUGUAUCAUUCAGUGAAGAGAAGAUUUCAUGGACUACCAAGAGCAGAACAAGUUACUCUUCAGCUCCCUUAACUGAAUCAAAUAUUAAAUCACAUCUUGCAAAAAACCAAGGCAAGUCUCACAGGCACCCAGAAAGCCAAGAAAGAAAGAAGGCCAGAUCUGAUUUAUUUAGGAAGAACAGCAGUCAUUGGGACCACGAUUACAGUUGUACACACAGCAAAGGGAAACGUGACAGAAAGAAGAGAGUGUAUGAUUAUGAGUCAGAAAGAUUGGAUUGUUUCCAAAGCAAACAUAAAUCAGCAUCAAAACCUCAUCAUGACGAUAUCAACUUCUAUUCUGAAAGAAAACAAAACCGGCCCUUUUUUUUUGCCUGUGUACCGGCAGACUCACUGGAGGUUAUACCCAAAACCAUUCGCUGGACUAUUCCCCCUGAAACCUUAAGGAAAAGAAACUUCAGAAUUCCCCUAGUGGCAAAGAUUUCAAGUUCUUGGAAUAUAUGGAGUUCCUCCAAAAAGUUGUUGGGGUCGCUCUCGGGGUCCCUUACUACCGUUUUUCAUAGCUGACAUUACCAUAGCUAAACUCCUCUGAAGUGGACAGCUGGUCGCUAUUGUGAUAUUCUGUGAAAAAUACAAUCAUAUAACAUCCAA